GUAGUGUUGUUGUUUUCAGCCUGCUGCUGCUGCUGCUGUUGCGGCUAGGGGAACCGUCGUGGGGAAGGAUGGUGUGCGAAAAAUGUGAAAAGAAACUUGGUACUGUUAUCACUCCAGAUACAUGGAAAGAUGGUGCUAGGAAUACCACAGAAAGUGGUGGAAGAAAGCUGAAUGAAAAUAAAGCUUUGACUUCAAAAAAAGCAAGAUUUGAUCCAUAUGGAAAGAAUAAGUUCUCCACUUGUAGAAUUUGUAAAAGUUCUGUGCACCAACCAGGUUCUCAUUACUGCCAGGGCUGUGCCUACAAAAAAGGCAUCUGUGCGAUGUGUGGAAAAAAGGUUUUGGAUACCAAAAACUACAAGCAAACAUCUGUCUAGAUGUAUUGAUGGAAUUUCUGGCUUUCUAAAUGAUUUUACUUUCUGCCUUGAAUUUUCAAGGCAUAGAUGUCAACUUACAGAAUAACAUGUUUUAAGAUAAUUAAGUUUAAACCAGAGAAUUUGAUUGUUACUCAUUUUGCUCUCAUGUUCUAAACAGCAACAGUGUAACUAGUCUUUUGUUGUAAAUGGUUAUUUUCCUUAUAAGAAUUUUAAGAACUAAGUGGCAAAUUCCAUGAAAAUAUUUCUCAGUUCUGUAUGCACUUUUAUUUAACAUUAUUCAUAUAAUUCUCCCCCCACCACUUUAUUUAUAGAUACUGCAAAAGUGAGAAGGAGAUAAUAGAUACUUUGCUCUGAAUUUGGCAUCCAGAGUUAACAUUUCUCCCCUCACUCCCUUGCUGGUGUCAUAGUUAUUAGAAUCAGCAGCCUCUUAACUAAUUGCGGUUUCAUAGGAUAUAUAAAUGUUUCAAGCCAUUAUUGCUGAAUGGUUCUUUAGUUAUUAACCUAGACCCAAAUCAAAGACCAGUUGGAUUUAUGAUAUUUUUUAUUUGUUCUUGCAGCCAAAGUGCCAGUUUCUUUAAUAUGUGACCAAGAACACAAGGAGCAUCCAUAUGGCCAAAUAAAUACACUGAAUUUUAGAAAAACAUAUUACUUUGAAUUCAAAUUGUCAUGAAAACCAGAACAGUGUUUGUCCAUGUUGCAUGUAAUGAAAAUAAAUCCCUGCUCUGAGAAAAGCUCUUUGAAGCAAAAACCAAACUUUUUUUUUUUUUUUUUUACCUCCUGUCUUGCCCCCUAAAAGAAAUAAAUAGAGCAAACAUCUUGACUCUCCCUUUUUAAAAUUUGUUUGUUUUUUUUUUUUUUUUUUGGAUACAAGAGCUCACUCUGUUGCCCAGGGUGGAGUGCAGAGGUAUCAUCAGGCUCUCUGCAGCCUCCAUCUGCUGGGCUCAAGCAAUUCUUCCCCCUCAGCCUCCUAAGUAGCUGGGGACUACAGGCGUGUGCCACUGUGCUCAGCUAGUUUUUAUUUUUAGUAGAGAUGAGGACUCACUAUGUUGCCCAAGCUGUUCUCGAACUUCUGAUCUCAAGCAAUCCUCUGGCCUCAGCCUUCCGAAGUGCUGGGAUACAGGUGUGAGCCACAGAACUUGGCCUCUCUCUUUUUUUUUUUUUUUUUUUUUUUUUUUUAACACUACAGGUUUCAAAUGAAUACUUUUCUUAUGUUGCCUUCAGAGGUUCAGGACUUCUGCUUUUAAAACCUGCAGCCUACCGUGGGAAACCAAAAAAGCAUUCCCUAUUUCCAACUGCAGUAUGUAUAAAUACAUAUCACUACAAAAUGUAUAGAAAGUGUGAUGAGAUACAUGAAUGGCAUUUUUAUUGGUCAUAACAUUUUGAUGAAAAGCAUUUAAAGUUUUAACUUUAUAAGGCUUUUCAAAAUGUGUUUUUCUGAGAUACAUUGUUAUUUAUUCAUAUCCAGAAAAAUUACAAGGAUAAUACAGAAUAUAAUAAAUAAUUUAUCUGAGAGCAGGAAGUAUCCUCUCAUGCUUAAUCAGUUUGGGGUUUUUAAUUAUAACACAGGAAACUCAUAACAGGACCUGGUCAGAGAGCAUCCCAGAUCCAUUAAAGAUUGGAUUCAUUGACUUGGAGAAAAGUACAUUUCUCAGGGAUCAGCUAGAAUCUGGACUUGCCUAACUCACAUUUCAUUUUUUUUGUUGUUGUUGUUGUUUUUAUAAUUUCAACUUUUAUUUUAGAUGUAGGGGUACAUGUGCAGGUGAGUUAUAUGGGUAUAUUUUGUGAUGCUGAGGUUUGGGGUACAAAUGAUCCUGUCACCCAGGUAGUGAGCAUAGAGUCCAACAGGUGGUUUUUCACCCCUUCCCUCCCCUCUUCCCUCCAGUAGUCCCCUAUGUCUGUUCUCAUUUUUAUGUCCAUGUGUACCCAUUGCUUAGUUCCCACUGAUAAGUGAGAACAUGCGGUCUUUGGUUUUCUGUUCCUGUGUAUAUUCACUAUAAUGACCUCCAGCUGCAUCCAUGUUGCUGCAAAAGACAUGAUUUUCAUUCUUUUUUAUGGCUGCAUAGUAUUCUGUGGUGUAUAUGUACCAAUUUUCUUUAUCCAGUCCACUAUUAAUGAGCAUCUAGGUUGAUUCUGUGUCUUUGCUGUUGUGAAUAGUGCUGUGAUGAAUAUGUGAGUGUAUGUGUCUUUUUGGUAGAACAAUUUAUUUUCAUUUGGAUUUAUAUCCAGUCAUGGGAUUGCUGGUUCAAAUGGUAGUUCUGUUUUAACUUCUUUGAGAAAUCUCCAAACUGCUUUCACAGUGGCUGAACUAAUUUGCAUUUCCAUCAGUGUAGGCGCAUUCUACACUGCACUGGCUUCUACAGUGUUGAAGCAUUCCGUUUUUCCCACAGCCUCACCAGCAUCUGUUAUUUUUUUGACUUUUUGAUAAUAGCCAUUCUGACUGGUGUGAGAUUGUAACUCAUUGUGGUUUUGAUUUGCAUUUAUCUGAUUAGUAAUGUUGAGCAUUUUUUCAUGUUUGUUAACCGCUUGUAUGUUGUCUUUUGAGAAGUGUCUGUUCAAGUCUUUUGGCAUUUUUUUAAUGGGUUUUUGUUUGUGUGUGUGUAUUUUUGUUUUUGUUUUUGUUUUGAGAUGGAGUUUCACUGUUGUCACCCAGGCUAGAGUGCAAUGGCACCAUCUCAGCUCACUGCAACCUCCACCUCCCGGGUUCAAGCGAUUCUCCUGCCCCAGCCUCCUGAGUUGCUGGGAUUACAGGUGCCUGCCACCAAGCGUGGCUAAUUUUGGUACUUUUAGUAGAGACAGGGUUUCACCAUGUUGGCCAGCCUGGUCUCGAAUUCCUGACCUCAGGUGAUCCACCCAUCUCAGCCUCCCAAAGUGCUGGGAUUACAGGAGUGAGCCACCACACCUGGCCACGAGUUACUUGGUUUUCGUUUUCUGAAUUGUUUUAGUUCCUUAUAGAUUUUGGACAUUAGACCUUUUUCAGAUGCACAGUUUGUGAAUAUUCUCUCCCAUUCUGUAGGUUGUCUGUUUACUGUAUUGAUAGUUCCUUUUGCGGUGCAGAAGCUCUUUAGUUUGAUUAGGUUCCACUUGUCAAUUUUUGUUUUUGUUGCAAUUGCUUUUGAGGACUUAGCCGUAAGUUCUUUCCCAUAGCUGAUGUCCAGAUGUUAUUUCGUAGGUUUUCUUCUAGGACUCUUAUAGCUUGAAGUCUUACAUUUAAAUCUUUUUUUUUUUUUUUCCCCAAAGACAGAGUCUCCUUCUGUUGCCCAGGCUGGAGUACAGUGGUACAAUCUUGGCUCACCACAACCUCCACCUCCCAGGCUCAAGCGAUUCUCAUGCCUCAGCCUCCCAACCUAACUGGGAUUACAGGCACAUGCCACCACGCCUGGCUAAUUUUUCUAUUUUUAGUAGGAAUGGGGUUUUACCAUGUUGGCCAGGCUGGUCUUGAAUUCCGAGCCUCAAGUGAUCCACCCACCUCAGUCUCCCAAAGUGCUGGGAUUACAGGCAUGAGCCACUGCACCCGGCCCCUUAUAUUUAAAUCUUUAAUCUAUCUUGAGGUAAUUUUAUAUAUAUGGUGAAAGGGGUCCAGUUUGAGUCUUCUGCAUAUGGCUAGACAGCUGUUCCAGCACCAUUUAUUGAAUUAGGGAAUCCUUUCUCUGUUGCUUAUUUUUGUUAACUUUGUCAAAGGUCAGAUGGCUGUAGGUGUGUAGCUUUAUUUCUGUCUGUUCCAUUCCAUUGGUCUAUGGGUCUGUUUUUAUAUCUGUACCAUGCUGUUUUGGUUACUGUAGCUUCCUUAUAGUAUAGUUUAACUCAGGUAAUGUGAUACCUCAGCUUUGUUUUAUUUGCUUAGGAUUGAUUUUUUGGUUCCAUAUGAAUUUUAGAAUGGAUUUUUUCUUUUUUUUUUUUUUUGAGACGGAGUCUUGCUGUGUCUCCCAGGCUCUGAGUGCAGCUGUGCAAUCUCAGCUCACUGCAACCUCUGCCUCCUGAGUUCAAGCAAUUCUCCUGCCUCAGCCUCCCAAAUAGCUGGGAUUACAGGAGCCCGCCAACCAUGCCCAGCUAAUUUAUGUAAUUUUAGUAGAGAUGGGGUUUCAUCAUCUUAGCCAGGCUGGUCUUGAACUCCUGACGUUGUGAUCCACCCGCCUCAGCCUCCCAAAGUGCUGGGAUUACAGGCGUGAGCCACUGGACCCGGCAGGAUUUUUCUAAUUCUGUGAAAAAUGAUGUUUGUAGUUUGAUAGGAAUAGCAUUGAAUCUGUGGAUUGCUUUGGGCAGUAUGGCCAUUUUAAUGAUAUUGAUUCUUCUAGCUCAUGAGCUUGGAAUGUUUUUCCAUUUGUUUGUGUCAUCUCUGAUUUCUUUCAGCGUGUUUUGUAGUUCUUGUCCAGCUCACAUUUUAUCUUCAUACUUUGAGUAGCCUCCUUCCAUGAAUGGAUCAUCCAGUGGCCGCACUUAGGUUCUCCUAUGAAGAUUUUUGUUGUAUUGUACCUCAGAACCAUCUCCAUAUUCUCUAAAUAAUAAUAAUGAUGGUCAUAAAUUGAAUAGAAGUAUUUACUAGAUGAGGAGGAAAACCCUAAAACAAAACAUGAACAUAAAAUAUUUUUAAAAGGAAGACAUACAAACAGACACUAUAACCAAAUAAGAUGACAGAAUUAAGGCCUUAUGCCACAGCCAGAGUUGAAAAAUGCAGAAAAAAAGUUUAAAAACAAGGAAUUAAAGCCAAACCUAACUUUUAUCAAAAUAAAUGUAAAAGUGAUGAAAGAAUCUGUUAAGAUAUCAGAUUGUAAUAUAAAAGAUACUAGAAACAAAUGCCAAUAGAACACUUAAGUACAUUUUAUAUAUUCAUCCAUUAGAAUAUAUAGCUGUCAGAAUGAUAGAAGAAUUACAUAUGUGUGCAAAAGUUUUUGUAUCCAUGUGGAAAACACAGGAAGCUAAUAGUACUGUUUUUCUCUGGAGUGGGUGUAAGGGUAGAGACUUAACUCUUUACAUCCUUAUGGCAGCCUUCGAAUACCUUUUAACUCCCAGUUCCCUUAACUGGGGGUGUGUAUCCUAGAAUCCUCGACCCAUUAGAAAGUAUAUUGUAGACAUCAUACUCUUUACCCUUUAACACUACACAUGCACUUCAUAAGAACAAGCAUGCUGUCUUACCCAAGUACAGCUAUCAAGUUCAGAAAUUUAACAUUGCCAUAAUACUUUACAGUCCAUAUUUCAAUUUCAUUUGCUGUUUUAUUGGUAAUUUUUUUCAGCUCCACGAUCCAGCCUAGGAUCAUAUGUUGUAUUGCCAUAACCCUCUAAUCUGGAGCAGUUCCUCAGCUUUUCUUUGUUUUUUAUAAUAGUAAUAUAUUUGAAAAAUACAGGACAGCUAAAGGAUAGAGUAUCCUUCUAUUUGGGUUUUUCUGAUGUUUCCUCAUGGUUAGAUUGGGGUAGUGCAGUGAGGGUUGAAAUGCUGUAAGUGAUAUGUAUUGCAGGUAUACAUCCAGAUGCACAGAAUGUCCAUUUGUCCCUUAUUGGUGAUGCUAAUUUUGAUCACUUGGGUAAGAUGUCCAGUUUCUCCAGUGUAUCGUUAUUGUUUUUCCUUUUGCAAUUAGUGGGUAAUUUGUGAGGAGAAACUUUGAGACCUUGUUGACAAUUCUGUUCCUCAUCAAAUCUACCCCUCCUAGGUUUAGCAUCCUUUGACGAUUCUUGUCUGAAUAAAUUUUUACUAGGAUGUUUCCAAAAUUGUGAUUGUUCUAACUCUAUUAUUAUUUCUGUAUUAAUUAGUCAUCAUUCUACUGUAAGGAAGAGGUUUCCCUUUAUCAUCAACUUCGAGUAAGUACUUUUUUCUGAGCCAUUUGAAUAUUCCUUACUAGAUGUGGUGCCUCUUUACCCCAAUUACUUAAGUUUGUAUUUCCAAAGAACAAGGGUGUUUUCCUGCAUAGCCAUAGCACAAUUACCAAAAUCAGAAAAUUAACAUUAAUACUUUACUAU